UAUAUAGUGAGAUUGCUGGAUCAUAUGGUAGUUCCAUUUUUAAUUUUUCUGAGGAACCACUGUAUUGUUUUCCAUCAUGGCUUUCCAAGAUAGUAUCACUUAAUGACUUCAAUUUUAAUUAAUGAUUGCAAAAAUGUAUGUAUUUUGAGCUACUUAGCCUUUUCUUCUGGAGGUUCUUGGCAGACACCAAAGUAACCCUUAUGGAUGAUGAGACUGAACUAUAACAAAACACCAAGUUCAAAAAAAAGAACACAUGGUCCCUGCCUCCAAAUGUUUAGUGAGAAAAAUAGAUUUACAAAUAUCUGCAUUACAAGAUAGUAUAAAUGGAGUCAUAGGGUAGAACAUCAAUAGUGUGCUACUGAAUGACAAAGGAAAGGAGAGGUUCAUUCAAGGCUAAGUGUGAAGAAAAGUUGUGGGGUGGGUGUAGCAAUUUAGGAAGAGGAUUUCCUUGAUGGAAAAGAGGCCUGCUGGAACAAGAGAAUAGCACAGAGAUAAGGAAGUCUAGUGUGUUUAUAGGAAGCAAAGCAGUUUGGAGUAGCUGAAACCUGGAAUUUAAGACAGAUAAGGCUGGGAGGUGGGAUGGGGCUAGAUUAUAGAGACUAUGACAUGUCAUGCUAAGAAAUUAAAAUAUGAUUGAACAUUAUUGGUAUAUUUACAUAAACAGUAUCAACAUCCUUAACUGUACUUUUUGCCUUUAAUUUCAGUUUUAUGAGUUUCCUUCUAAAAUAAGUAGUUGAUUAAAAUCUCAAUAUUCACUUCCUAUCAGUUUCUUUCAAUCAGUAAAAGAAUAAUGUAUUCCUAAUAUCCUUCAAUGCUUUAUCUAAAUCCAACAGUGUUUUACCCCCAAACCUGCAUUCCUAUGAUAUUAAUAGCUCUUAGCUUGAUUAAAACUUCCGAUAGAAAAACACUUCCACUUUCCUGGGGCAAUAUGCAGUGUAUAGUCAUUUUCUAUUCUCUGUUGCAAUCAUUAAUAAUAAUAAUUAAUGUUUAUUAAACAUGUUAUGUCAAGGGAGCCACAUAGCCUUAUGUUAUCUAGGGAGGCAUUAUUUUGAUCUUAGACUGAGAAUUUUUACAAGGUCACACAACUAAGUAAAGGGACCAAGGAGUCUACCCCCAGAGUCUGUGCUUUGAACUAUUGUACUAUCAUGUAACGGGGCAUAGUGUAUGAUAAUUAUUGUUAAUAUUAGAUAGAAACUGGGCCUGAUUCCUGUAGCAGGACUGUUUCUCUGUUUUUUUUUUCUUUGCAUCUUAAUUUUCAUCAUUUGGAUUAAUUUUAUCUUACACUUUCAGUGACGGGACAUAUUUUAAUGUUUUAAUACACUUUUAAACUACUCAUGGGAUCUCGUAUUUUUAUGACCCACCCAAAAGAAACUCUUAAACUCUGAGAAGAGACAGGAUGUGGGACGAAAAAAAAUGUUAGCAACAGUGAUGGCACAAGAUGUGAAGACCAGGCCUCUGGAAGAAUGUUGAUUACCAAUAUUCUCAUGAUUCCCAAUAAACUCCCCAAAUCACCAGAUCUUUUUGCAUUUCAGCAUCCCAUAUAUUUUUCUGUGUGUCUUGAUUUUUUUAUUAUGAAGGUAAUACAGUAAACAUACUACUUUGUACAUGACAUACUAAAGUAUGUAUUUAGACAACAGAUCAAACAUCACAUGAUCAUGUAUAAAUUGUGCAAAACGUUUGCUAACUGAAAGAACACGUCAGUGUUAUUAUCAUAGAUUUCUUCACCAGAACACUAUUCUCAGGCCAAGCUCUGGAGGAGAGGGUUGUGUGGAGUAGAGAGAAGCUGAAAUGAGAGCCUGGCAGUCCAGUGACCCUGGUAACAGUGUGGGACACAGGGAGAUGAUGAUACCAAUGUAUCUCAGUGUCUGGCCCUCACUCUGCCUAAAUUUAACUGUUACAUCUUUAUUUUUGUAUUUACUUUGUUAAAUAUUUGGACCUUUCCAUCUUUUCUCAGGCUCUGAGUGGUUUACAGAUUCUGCUAUUUUCACUUUUGAGUUUGAGAGUAGGACUUAGAAAUAGAUGACUCUUCAAUGGAUUGGUGAGUAAAGGAUCCUGAAACUGUUCUCUCCUUUAGCAUGACGUCUCUCAACUUCAGUUUCCUCAUGGGUAGAUUGAGGGAUUGAAUAAGAUAAGUGGUGGCAAUCACAAAUCUUCACAAGGUUUACCCGGAUGAGACAGGCAUCAUAAAUGAGCAAAGAAGACUGGGGGCAGUGGUUGGGUAGUAGGUGUGUGGAGGUAUGGGGGAUAGCACAGGUGAAACUAAAUGCAAGGCAACGUUAGUCCUGCGUCAGGGAGAUAUUAGGGAGUAGAAGGACCUGGAGAGAAAAUGCCUCAUCCAAUGAGAGCCAGACUUACUCAGUUCCAGUUAAUUGUUAUGUAAGAAUGAGGGCCCAGUGUUAUCAGAACUUUCAAUGUUUUGAGAGAAUCCUAAAGUUCAGAUUUUUAUGUGAAAUCUAUUCUAGUGUUAAAACAUCAGCAAUUUGGCCGGGCGCAGUGGCUCACGCCUGUCAUCCCAGCACUUUGGAGGCAGAGGCGGGCGGAUCACGAGGUCAGGAUAUUGAGACCAUCCUGGCUAACAGGGCGAAACCCCGUCUCUACUAAAAAAAUACCAAAAGAAUUAGCCAGGCAUGGUGGCGGGCACCUGUAGUCCCAGCUACCUGGGAGGCUGAGGCAGGAGAAUGGCGUGAACCCGGGAGGUGGAGCUUGCAGUGAGCCGAGAUCUCGCCACUGCACUCCGGCCUGGGCGACACAGCAAGACUUCGUCUCAAAAAAAAAACGAAAAAAAAAAAUCAGCAAUUCAUUCAAAUUUACUAAAAACAAAACCAAAAACAUUGAGUCCGCCAAACGAAACACAUUAAGAGACCAGACUUGGCCAGAUUUGGCCUGAGUGGUGCCAAAGUUUCCAAAAUUCCUUCUGACUUCAGACUUUUGUGAUCCUAUAUAGCCAAUUUCUUCCCCUUUUGCUAAAACAUAUGGUAGUACUCCCUGUAUCCAAAUUAUGACAGCUUUGGAGGAGCUCUUUGGCAAAUGCUAGACUAUAAAAAAUCUACAAGGCCUCGAAGAUUAAAAAAUAUCCUUUUUUCAUAGCCGCACUAUUGAUAAAAUUCAGAGGCCUCAUACCACGGGAGGCCAUGAUAGGAGAAUUGCUUCAGCCCAGCAGUUUGAGACCAGCUUGGGUAUCAUAGUGAGACUUCGUCUCUACAAAAAAUGAAAAAUUAGCGGUCAUAGUGGCACCUGCCUGUAGUCCUAGCUAUUUGGGAAGCUGAGGUAGCAGGAUCAUUUGAGCUUGGGAGGUCAAGGCUGCAGUGAUGAGCUGUGAUUGCACCACUGCACCCCAGCCUGGCAACACAGCAAGGACCUGUCUCAAAAAAUCAGAGGCUCCAGAAGUUAAUUACCUGUAUUUAUUGUCCCUUUCAGGAACGAUUAGUGUGAUUUAGUUCCAAGAUUCAGAACUGCUCCUCUAAAUAUUUUACUUCCUGUUCUGCCUUUCCAUCUUAAUGUGAAAGAAUCAAUUUUGGUUUCCACUUGGAUGAGGGGUAUUUAUAGGCUUGGCUGAUGGUGUUCAGACAAAGCAAUCUUCAUUGUCUUUAACCUGGCAAUAUUUCACCACGUAUUCUGUCCCUCUUCCUUAACAGAGCUAUCUGGGGAUGUUCUUGAAUUUCAACUAGAUGGAUAAAUUAAGUGUUUGACUUGUAGAAGUUAAUAUGGCAAUUUCGAUUUUUUUAAAAAGCUAUUUAUAUGGAUCCAAAAAAUAAAAAGGUAAACAUAAUGAAUGGAUUUGCAGUGAAAUUCUUUAAUACAAGUGUGUUUUUAAAGCUGAGUUUCUUGGAUUUGACUGGCUGGGAUGUGUUAUUUGCUUUAUGUCAAUGAGCUAUUCUACAAACAAGUGGGCCUGACUUAAAGUUCAGAGCAGAUGUUGACAAUGAGAAGGAAGCAUUUGAGUACAUAAAACAAGAAUGACAUGUUGAGAGAAACCACAUACCUUACUGUGACUGAGCUGACUACAGAGGACAAACAAGAGGCUCUGAAUGACAGUUUUGAGCCACGAUUUGCCCUUGUCCUAGCCCCAGUAAUGAGUCAGCCCCCACCCUUUCACAUCAGCGAGUAUGUUAACCAUCACUGAAUGUUUAACAUUUAAAACCGAAUCGGAAAGAAUCAGGUAAUUAUUUGAUCAUUACAGCCAUGUCAUCCGAUGUUAUAUUGGUAAAAGAUUUGGAUUUUAAUUUUUUUACUCAUGUAUUUGGCUAGCUUUUCAGAUUCAAUGGUGGAGACAGACUCUAAGCUCCAGAGAGGAAGGGGCCACAUCUCCUUCACCCCACAAUGCCUUCUAAAUGCACUCAGUUCAUUUUGUUGAAUGAAAGAUCUUUGAUUAAUCAUUUGAAUAUAUAGGAGAUUUUAGGUAAGUAGGCUUUCAAUGCAUUCAUUCAUUCAUUCCAUACAGAUUUGUUGAGCUUUCCCUAUGUGCCAAUCAUAAUUCUUAGUGCUAGGCAUAUGUGAUAGACUUGUGGGCUAGUCCCUUAACAAAUAACAAUCUAUUGUAAUAAAUAUUAUGGCAGAGAUGCUUAAAUCGGUGUGAGACCUUGGAGGAGGAAUGACUGAUGUAGAGUUUCACAGAUGGCAUCAAGAUGAGAGAAACAGUUUGGGCUCAGUCUUGAAGGAAGAGUAGAAUUGGAGAAAGGCAUUCCAGCUGCCUCCAGCUACUAACAGGAACUGAAGAGUCAAAGCUUGGACGAGGGAGGGAGCAUAGCUAAAAUGCUGAGUCGUGAGCUGUGGGUUGGGGGGCACAGAUUUGUUGGACAUCCUAGCAUUACAGACUUUUAGAAGAAAGAAUCAGGUAACUGGCUAGUUAUUUAAAGAUCUGGAUAUCUGAUGUCAUAUGAACACAACAUGGUUUUAUAAAACCAAUGCUUUCAUUUUUGUUUAUAAUUUUUGAAUAACAUUAUAGUUUUAGUGAUGGACAACUGUAAGCUUCAUGAGGGAAAGAAUGAUUGUCAUUGAUAUCUUAGUGUCCUUUUGUAAUUAAUGAAAUAAAACCUUGUGCUCUGCUAAUGGGUAAACUGUGGGUAAUGAGGAACCAUGGAAGGAUCUGAAAAAUUGGAAGCAGAAUUGAGAUGACCAGAGAGCCACGGUUUAGGAAGAUGGAUCUGGGAGCAGCUCGGCAGAUGCCCUGCAGCAGGGAGACAGUGUAAGCUGAGGGAUCCACCUGUAGGCAGUUGUGAUGGUCCAGGCAUUCGCAGAAAAGAUGGAGAGGAAGAGUCUGAUUGCAGAACUCUUUGGGGGACCCUAGGAUGCUGGAGACGGGUAGCUGGGAUUCAAGGAAGAGCUGGAAUGCAAUGAAGUGGAGGCUUUGUGCUUGGGCAAAUGGAAGUACGGUCAUGACAGUUUUCCAGGUAAAAUUCAGGAGGAGAAAUUAAGAAUUGAGUUUGAGGGGCCUGGGCACAUCCAGUUGAGAUCUUGACAUGGAAAAUGGUGAAAAAUUCGUUAGAAAUGUGGAUCUGGAGUUCUGAAGAGAGGUCAGAGCUGGGGAUGGAGACUUCAGACUUCUUGCUUGAGUAUCUGUGAUCACUUGGUGGCGUUAGAGAGAGCCUGGGAGAGUCUUGCAGUGGGCUCACGAAAGCCAAGGGGGCAGUGGUUCAUAAAAACAGAGACGUAAACAGUGUCAAGAAUGAGGAGGCUGUGCUGACAAACUGUGAGGAUGCAGGGAAUGCCAUAGUGAAACACUUUUUAUUGUCUAGGUGCAUCAGAAGCCAGAAAUCACUGAGUAGAGGAAUGAUGAGAAGGUGAGGAAGCAGAGGACCUGCAGAGAAACGCCUCCUGAUUUUGUCUUACAAUGGAACUUAAAAAGUCGCCUGACGGUGGAUGGGGCUGGGUGAUUGUGUUUGUCUCCUUCCUUACUCAGUUUUUGUGUUACGGAUCCCCACUAGCUGUUGGAGUCCUGUACAUAGAAUGGCUGGAUGCCUUUGGUGAAGGAAAAGGAAAAACAGCCUGGGUUGGAUCCCUGGCAAGUGGAGUUGGCUUGCUUGCAAGUCCUGUCUGCAGUCUCUGUGUCUCAUCUUUUGGAGCAAGACCUGUCACAAUCUUCAGUGGCUUCAUGGUGGCUGGAGGCCUGAUGUUGAGCAGUUUUGCUCCCAAUAUCUACUUUCUGUUUUUUUCCUAUGGCAUUGUUGUAGGUCUUGGAUGUGGUUUAUUAUACACUGCAACAGUGACCAUUACGUGCCAGUAUUUUGACGAUCGCCGAGGCCUAGCGCUUGGCCUGAUUUCAACAGGUUCAAGCGUUGGCCUUUUCAUAUAUGCUGCUCUGCAGAGGAUGCUGGUUGAGUUCUAUGGACUGGAUGGAUGCUUGCUGAUUGUGGGUGCUUUAGCUUUAAAUAUAUUAGCCUGUGGCAGUCUGAUGAGACCCCUCCAAUCUUCUGAUUGUCCUUUGCCUAAAAAAAUAGCUCCAGAAGAUCUACCAGAUAAAUACUCCAUUUACAAUGAAAAAGGAAAGAAUCUGGAAGAAAACAUAAACAUUCUUGACAAGAGCUACAGUAGUGAGGAAAAAUGCAGGAUCACGUUAGCCAAUGGUGACUGGAAACAAGACAGCCUACUUCAUAAAAACCCCACAGUGACACACACAAAAGAGCCUGAAACGUACAAAAAGAAAGUUGCAGAACAGACAUAUUUUUGCAAACAGCUUGCCAAGAGGAAGUGGCAGUUAUAUAAAAACUACUGUGGUGAAACUGUGGCUCUUUUUAAAAACAAAGUAUUUUCAGCCCUUUUCAUUGCUAUCUUACUCUUUGACAUCGGAGGGUUUCCACCUUCAUUACUUAUGGAAGAUGUAGCAAGAAGUUCAAACGUGAAAGAAGAAGAGUUUAUUAUGCCACUUAUUUCCAUUAUAGGCAUUAUGACAGCAGUUGGUAAACUGCUUUUAGGGAUACUGGCUGACUUCAAGUGGAUUAAUACCUUGUAUCUUUAUGUUGCUACCUUAAUCAUCAUGGGCCUAGCCUUGUGUGCAAUUCCAUUUGCCAAAAGCUAUGUCACAUUGGCGUUGCUUUCUGGGAUCCUAGGGUUUCUUACUGGUAAUUGGUCCAUCUUUCCAUAUGUGACCACGAAGACUGUGGGAAUUGAAAAAUUAGCCCAUGCCUAUGGGAUAUUAAUGUUCUUUGCUGGACUUGGAAAUAGCCUAGGACCACCCAUCGUUGGUUGGUUUUAUGACUGGACCCAGACCUAUGAUAUUGCAUUUUAUUUUAGUGGCUUCUGCGUCCUGCUGGGAGGUUUUAUUCUGCUGCUGGCAGCCUUGCCCUCUUGGGAUACAUGCAACAAGCAACUCCCCAAGCCAGCUCCAACAACUUUCUUGUACAAAGUUGCCUCUAAUGUUUAGAAGAAUAUUGGAAGACACUAUUUUUGCUAUUUUAUACCAUAUAGCAACGAUAUUUUAACAGAUUCUCAAGCAAAUUUUCUAGAGUCAAGACUAUUUUCUCAUAGCAAAAUUUCACAAUGACUGACUCUGAAUGAAUUAUUUUUUUUUAUAUAUCCUAUUUUUUAUGUAGUGUAUGCGUAGCCUCUAUCUCGUAUUUUUUUCUAUUUCUCCUCCCCACACCAUCAAUGGGACUAUUCUGUUUUGCUGUUAUUCACUAGUUCUUAACAUUGUAAAAAGUUUGACCAGCCUCAGAAGGCUUUCUCUGUGUAAAGAAGUAUAAUUUCUCUGCCGACUCCAUUUAAUCCACUGCAAGGCACCUAGAGAGACUGCUCCUAUUUUAAAAGUGAUGCAAGCAUCAUGAUAAGAUAUGUGUGAAGCCCACUAGGAAAUAAAUCAUUCUCUUCUCUAUGUUUGACUUGCUAGUAAACAGAAGACUUCAAGCCAGCCAGGAAAUUAAAGUGGCGACUAAAACAGCCUUAAGAAUUGCAGUGGAGCAAAUUGGUCAUUUUUUAAAAAAAUAUAUUUUAACCUACAGUCACCAGUUUUCAUUAUUCUAUUUACCUCACUGAAGUACUCGCAUGUUGUUUGGUACCCACUGAGCAACUGUUUCAGUUCCUAAGGUAUUUGCUGAGAUGUGGGUGAACUCCAAAUGGAGAAGUAGUCACUGUAGACUUUCUUCAUGGUUGACCACUCCAACCUUGCUCACUUUUGCUUCUUGGCCAUCCACUCAGCUGAUGUUUCCUGGGAAGUGCUAAUUUUACCUGUUUCCAAAUUGGAAACACAUUUCUCAAUCAUUCCGUUCUGGCAAAUGGGAAACAUCCAUUUGCUUUGGGCACAGUGGGGAUGGGCUGCAAGUUCUUGCAUAUCCUCCCAGUGAAGCAUUUAUUUGCUACUAUCAGAUUUUACCACUAUCAAAUAUAAUUCAAGGGCAGAAUUAAACGUGAGUGUGUGUGUGUGUGUGUGUGUGUGCUAUGCAUGCUCUAAGUCUGCAUGGGAUAUGGGAAUGGAAAAGGGCAAUAAGAAAUUAAUACCCUUAUGCAGUUGCAUUUAACCUUAAGAAAAAUGUCCUUGGGAUAAACUCCAAUGUUUAAUACAUUGAUUUUUUUUCUAAAGAAAUGGGUUUUAAACUUUGGUAUGCAUCAGAAUUCCCUAUAGAUCUUUUUGAAAAUAUAGGUACCUGGGUAUCACACAUAGAACUUUUAAUUCUGCUGGUGUAGGCUGUUGCCCAAACAUCUAUAAUUUUACUGAGCUCUUCAAGUGAUUCUGAUAACACAGCCUGGAUUGAGAAUUUUUAUAAGAUUGGCAAUGGAAAAACAUUUAUUCUUUUAAAUAAUAAUUUUUUUAAAACCCAAGAGGUCAGGGGAUUUUAUAAACCAAUAGCCAAGUGUUCUUUAAAUAGGAGGCACCCUUCCCAUUGUGCCAAAAUCAUCUUUUCAUUUAUUUUGAAAUUUGUAUGAUUAUUUUAUACUUGUAUGUUGCCUUUCUUCGAAGGCGCCUGAAGCACUUUAUAAACACAAAUCCUCACAAUACCUCUGUGAGGUAGGUAAAUAGUACUUUUCUAUGUAGUAAACCUGGAAUAUGGAGAAUUUCAUAACAGUUCAUUCUACUUAAUAAUGCAAUAAUGGAGCUCCAAGUUGUCUUGGACUUCUACACCACACUCAGACUUCUGGAAAGUUUUCUGUACCUCAUUCUUUAGUCCCUGUCAAGGUUAGUAAAUAAAAUAAGUGACAUAAAAAAAAAAAAAACUAAACUACUUGUUGUGUUGAAAGUUCCUUUUUGCCAGUUAUGUUCAGGAAACCCAAUAACCUGAAAAAGUUUGACUUUGAUGUGACAUCUUCAUAUUCAUCAAUGCUGAUAAUUGUCCAAAGGCAUCUUCACUAUGUCUGCUAAAUAACAUCCAAUGUGGGCGUUAUCUGUUGUCUAGGGGAUGAAUUUUAAGUUACAAUAAAAUAUUUUUCUUUGUUUUGCA